CUAUGUUGCGCAGGUGGGUCUUGACUCCUAGGCUCAAGCGAUCCUUCUGCUUUGGCUUCCCAGAGUGCUGAGAUUUCACCCUGUGCUUUUUGAACCAAAGUUCUGGAUUCAAUAUUUGUCCUUGUUAAAUAUCACAUUAUUAUAUGUGGCCCAAUCUUCCUCACUUUCUUACAGCCUCCAUCAUGUCAUCCAAACAGUCACUUUCCCAGGCAGCCCCAUGAAUAGUCACAGCUCUGACAACCCAGGUGUUUUGUGUUUGCAUUACAAACUCUUACAAGCCAAGGAUCAAGCCUGUGACACUCCGCUAGCGACAUUCCAGGGAGACAAGUAUCCGUUGAUUUGUUGAUUUGGAUCUUUGGUGCAUCCAGCCCGCAAUUCCCCAUCAUUCCUGCAAGAGUUUCACAACUGACCUUGGGUGCCUCUGACAGCUGCUGCAGGAAACAUGGCCAAGUUUGCCCUGAAUCAGAACCUGCCCGACCUGGGCGGCCCCCGCCUGUGCCCGGUCCCCGCCGCCGGGGGCGCACGCAGCCCGAGCUCGCCCUACUCGGUGGAGACGCCCUACGGCUUCCACCUGGACCUGGACUUCCUCAAGUACAUAGAGGAGCUGGAGCGUGGCCCCGCUGCCCGCCGCGCCCCGGGACCCCCGACCUCGCGCCGUCCCCGCGCGCCCCGGCCCGGCCUCGCGGGCGCACGUAGCCCAGGCGCCUGGACAUCCAGCGAGUCCCUGGCCAGUGACGACGGUGGAGCACCGGGCAUACUCUCCCAGGGCGCGCCCUCGGGGCUCCUGAUGCAGCCGCUGUCGCCGCGCGCGCCCGUGCGCAACCCGCGCGUCGAGCACACGCUCCGGGAGACCAGCCGGCGGCUGGAGCUGGCGCAGACACACGAGCGCGCGCCCAGCCCCGGCCGCGGGGUCCCGCGCAGCCCACGCGGGUCCGGCCGCAGCAGCCCCGCCCCUAACCUUGCCCCUGCUUCGCCCGGCCCUGCCCAACUGCAGCUGGUGCGCGAGCAGAUGGCCGCGGCGCUGCGGCGCCUGCGCGAGCUCGAGGACCAGGCGCGAACGCUGCCCGAGCUGCAGGAGCAGGUGCGCGCGCUGCGCGCCGAGAAGGCGCGGCUGCUGGCCGGGCGCGCGCAGCCCGAGCCGGACGGGGAGGCUGAGACGCGCCCGGACAAGCUCGCCCAGCUGCGGCGGCUCACCGAGCGCCUGGCCACCUCCGAGCGCGGCGGCCGUGCCAGGGCCAGCCCCCGGGCUGACAGCCCAGACGGCCUGGCUGCAGGGCGCAGCGAGGGCGCGCUCCAGGUCCUCGACGGGGAGGUCGGGAGUCUCGAUGGGACGCCCCAGACCCGGGAGGUGGCCGCCGAGGCCGUGCCCGAGACCCGAGAAGCGGGUGCCCAGGCCGUGCCGGAGACCCGGGAGGCCGGCGUGGAGGCUGCCCCCGAGACCGUGGAGGCGGACGCGUGGGUGACCGAGGCGCUGCUGGGGCUGCCUGCGGCCGCCGAGCGCGAGCUAGAGCUGCUGCGCGCCAGUCUGGAGCACCAGCGCGGGGUGAGUGAGCUUCUGCGGGGCCGGUUGCGGGAGCUGGAGGAAGCCCGCGAGGCUGCGGAGGAGGCAGCGGCGGGGGCCCGGGCCCAGCUACGCGAGGCCACCACCCAGACCCCGUGGAGCUGUGCCGAAAAGGCCGCGCAGACCGAGUCCCCGGCAGAGGCGCCCUCCUUGACUCAGGAGAGCUCGCCCGGAUCCAUGGACGGAGACAGGGCCGUGGCGCCCGCGGGCAUCCUCAAAUCCAUCAUGAAGAAGAGAGACGGCACACCUGGUGCCCAACCCAGCUCCGGACCCAAGAGCCUGCAGUUUGUUGGGGUCCUCAACGGAGAGUACGAGAGCUCCUCCAGCGAGGACGCCAGCGACAGCGAUGGCGACAGCGAGAACGGUGGCGCCGAGCCCCCGGGUAGCUCCUCGGGCUCCGGGGAUGACAGCGGCGGGGGAUCCGACUCGGGCACCCCUGGCCCUCCCAGCGGCGGGGACAUCCGGGACCCUGAGCCCGAGGCGGAGGCAGAGCCUCAGCAGGUGGCACAGGGGAGGUGCGAGCUGAGCCCGCGUCUGAGGGAGGCGUGCGUAGCGCUGCAGCGGCAGCUGAGCCGGCCCCGCGGAGUAGCCAGCGACGGCGGCGCAGUGCGCCUCGUGGCCCAGGAGUGGUUUCGAGUGUCCAGCCAGCGGCGCUCUCAGGCGGAGCCCGUGGCCAGGAUGCUGGAAGGGGUGAGGCGCCUGGGACCCGAACUGCUGGCGCACGUGGUGAACCUGGCGGAUGGCAACGGGAACACGGCCCUGCACUACAGUGUGUCCCACGGGAACCUGGCCAUCGCAAGCCUGCUCCUGGAUACGGGGGCCUGCGAGGUCAACCGCCAGAACCGAGCCGGCUACUCGGCCCUCAUGCUGGCUGCACUCACCUCUGUGAGGCAGGAAGAGGAGGACAUGGCUGUGGUCCAGAGACUCUUCUGCAUGGGUGAUGUCAAUGCCAAGGCCAGUCAGACGGGGCAGACAGCCCUCAUGCUGGCCAUCAGCCAUGGCCGACAGGACAUGGUGGCAACCCUACUGGCGUGUGGGGCUGAUGUGAAUGCGCAGGAUGCGGAUGGGGCCACAGCGCUGAUGUGUGCCAGUGAGUAUGGGCGCCUGGACACCGUGCGGCUGCUGCUCACCCAGCCAGGCUGUGACCCUGCCAUCCUGGACAAUGAGGGCACCAGUGCCCUGGCCAUCGCCCUGGAGGCUGAGCAGGAUGAGGUGGCCGCUCUGCUACAUGCCCACCUGAGCUCGGGCCAGCCCGACACCCAGAGCGAGUCACCCCCUGGCUCCCAGACAGCCACACCUGGUGAAGGAGAAUGCGGUGACAAUGGAGAGAACCCCCAGGUUCAGUAAGCUGCCUCGUCUGGCUCACUACACCUAGCUGUGGGGAGAUCUCCUCGUCAGUCACCUCAGCCUUUGGCGCACAGAAGGGUCCAGGGUCCCCUGCUCAGAGGCUAACACUGGCCGAAGAGAAAGGCAAUUUCAGUUGGGGUGACUGUGGCAGGAAGGGGCUCACUCUGGCCCCACCAAGGUGAGGUGGGGACCAAGUGAUAGAGCCCUGAUCCACCCACUCUCUGAAACUUCUUUGCUAAUAAAACAUUCCUACUA